AGCACGUCCUCAGCCGCCGAGGAGCCAUCAGCUUCAGCUCCAGCUCCGCUCUCUUCGGCUGCCCCAAUCCCCGGCAGCUCUCUCAGGUAAUCGCCGCCGCCGGGCCCACACUUGAGGGCUUCUCUCUUUUGUUUCCCUCUGCCCACCCAGCUUCACCUCCUCUACAACCCCCAGCCCGCGCAUUGUCCAUUGUCUGGGGAUUUCUAGGCUGGCCUUUCGAUUGCAGAGCCUUUUCUUUGAAUAUUCCUGGCUGUCCCCCCUCAGUUCUCCAGCCUCCCCAAAACCCCACCCUGGUGGGUUCCGGGAUCCUCUCAUCAGACCCUCCCCAGGCUCGUCACCCUCUGUGCCCAGCAGUUUAAGCCUCAGGAAUGACCGCCCUUGUCUUUUUCGGUCUGGAAGUUGAGUCUUUAUUCCUUAGUCGUGGCCCCAGGGUACACCUGUGCUCCCCCGCCUUGCAACAUACCUGUCCCCCUUCCCAUACACACAACUGUACGGGGUUCGCGCCUCUCCUCCCCCAGCUCCCGCGCGCCCCGCGGCGCUCGCCUGGUCCUGCGGUUCCCUCUGAACAAUAGGCCUAGAUGCCCCGUUGCUGUAGUCUCCCCGACUCCUUCGUUUCUGUGGCUGGGCUGUACUGGGUAUCAGAGGAACAAGUCUGCAAAGUUCAUAGCCAGGAAUCAGUUUUGUUUUUAAUUUGAUAAGGAGAUUUUAGGAGAGAAACUACUGAUGUACACUCAUGGGAAGACUUUGAGUGGUCCAAUACCAGUUGCUCCUGAGCAUUUCUGUUUUUUUCCUGUGGUGAUGCCGUUGGCCCAAUUCCUUAGGUUUGGCUAAUUUUGAUUGUCAGACUUAAAACAGAGAGGUGAAAAGAAUUUUGUUUACAUCUGAACUGAGUGCCCUCACUUUCUGCUGCCAGAAGUUAUGGCUAAUGAUCACUUUUAUUAAUCAAAUAUAUUUUUCCUAUUGGCUAAUACUAUCUUUUAUGGGAGUAUAUUUUCUCUCUCCAGUUAUAUUGUAUCUUGAGCAAGGUGUGUGUGUGUGUGUGUGUGUGUGUGUGUGUGCAGGUAGUGUGGACAGCACCUGGUAGAAAUUUUGCGUGUAAUAAGUGUCUAGUAAAUAUUUGUCAUUUACUUCUUUGCCUAAAGUGUUUGUAGAAGGAGCAAGAGCCUAUAUUUGGGUCUCUCUCUGAAUCCUUUUUAUUUAAACUAAAACUUAUUUCACAGCACAAGGUAGUAUGCUAAUGAGGUCAGAGCAGACUUGUGAAAAUUACUAUAAUGUGUCAUUUAGAAUAAUAUUACAUGGUUAUUUAUUUUGAAGGUUAGACCUGUGAUCUGCCUUUUUAGUACCACUUAAAGCAUGUUCAGAUUCCAGAAUUAAUGUUGAGGAAAUCUUAAUGCACUGCUGAAGAAGGUUUUUAAUAGUAGUAGUUAAAGGUUUUUAAUGGUAGUAACUUUUUUUACUUCUAAAUAUUAUUUUACUUCCUCAGAUCAGCAGGCACAUGACUAGCAACUCAUUUCCAGUUAUGUCUGAAUAAUAAAGGCAAUCACUGAUUAUUUAUACAAUUAUAAAACAUGAAUAAAGUUCUUGUGCUCUCUGAGAAGAAAAUGAAUGAGAAGGAAGAUUCCAAGGGAUUAAAAUGAGGCUGAUGCCAGGGGUUUUUCCUGAUGUCUUAAUUAAUCCACAGAGACCAAUUUUAAGCUCCACUUCUUGAUUCAUUUUUCCAGCCUUAGGUUUAAAUGGGUAAUGGAAUUUUAAAAAUAUGAUUGUGGCAGAUGAAGCAAAUAUUGUAGAAUUACACCAUAUUUUGCUAACCCUUACAACUUUUAAAAAAAUUUCUGAACCCCAAAGUGAAGUAUACAGGAACUUCUUAAACUUUGGACAGAAAUUUUCCUCAAUUAACCCUUUUUUUUCUAUUAACAUUGUGGUAAAUGUAAACUUAGUGGAUGCAGAGAUGGACAUACUUAUCAUUAUCAAGACUUUGCAUAUCAUUUAAUAAUAAAGCAUAUGUUGAUAUUGAUUUCUUUAGGCCUAGAUGUGAAUUUGUAAUAGGAAAAAAAAAAAGGAGACAGAAAACCUUGGAAUCCUGCUCAGAACUUGUAAAAUAAACAUUUGGUUAAUCAAAUGCUUUCUUUACCCUUAAAUUUUUAGUUCGUAAGCCUGAAGGUACAGAAGUUAUAAAAAGUUUAACUGGUUUUGUAAUUUUAAGAUACUUAGGAAAAAAAACCCUUUUUUUUUUAAAAAAAAGACAUUAAGUAAAAUAGUUACAGUUUUUGUACUUUAAAAUAUGCUUAAAACUGGCAACCUUCCUUUUCAUUUCCUUAUUGUCACCAUAGUAUUGGAGCCCAGCUCAUAGUAGGUACUUAAUAAAUAUUUGUUGAAUGAAUGAAUAGGUAAUGAAAUUAUCUCUGACUGAGCAUCAGUUUUAAAUAUGAAAACAAUAUGGAGCAUGAAGGUACAGCACAAAUUCAUUUAUCCAAAACUUGGUUUGGAACUUGUAACUGCAGACCAUAACGAUUCCAGGAAUACACAGAAAAGACCGAGUGACCAAAAUUGAUUUGGAGAUCGUCUUAAAGCCGGUGUGUUUUAGGCAAAGUUCUGACACAACUUGUUUUCAAGUAGCAGCAAAUUUGAAGUGGGGUGGGAGGCUGCCAGAGUCAGUUCACACUGACAGCAGCAAAGGUUGACAGCAGACACACCAAAAGCCAGGGAUCAGAAGAAAAACUCUUAGAAGCCAGCAACUUUUACAAGCACCCUGGGACAUUUAGUUGAGGGGCUUGAGUGUUGUAUAACACAAUAAUUUUUAGUCAGAAUAAUGUUAAUAGAGCCUGUUUUUAAAAGUUGAAAGAUUCGUACUGUUUUUUUGUUUUUAAAAAGAUUUCCAUGCCAAAGAGUUUUAAGUAUUGAUGCUGAACUGAAAUGGACAAGCUUGAGUUACCUGGAAAAUUCAUUUAUGUGGAUGGAACACCAGCUCUUCCAAGGAUGCCAAAGGCGUGGAGCUAUUUCCUAUGACAGUUCUGAUCAGACUGCAUUAUACAUUCGUAUGCUAGGAGAUGUACGUGUAAGGAGCCGAGCAGGAUUUGAAUCAGAAAGAAGAGGUUCUCACCCAUAUAUUGAUUUUCGUAUUUUCCACUCUCAAUCUGAAAUUGAAGUGUCUGUCUCUGCAAGGAAUAUCAGAAGGCUACUAAGUUUCCAGCGAUAUCUUAGAUCUUCACGCUUUUUUCGUGGUACUGCGGUUUCAAAUUCCCUAAACAUUUUAGAUGAUGAUUAUAAUGGACAAGCCAAGUGUAUGCUGGAAAAAGUUGGAAAUUGGAAUUUUGAUAUCUUUCUAUUUGAUAGACUAACAAAUGGAAAUAGUCUAGUAAGCUUAACCUUUCAUUUAUUUAGUCUUCAUGGAUUAAUUGAGUACUUCCAUUUAGAUAUGAUGAAACUUCGUAGAUUUUUAGUUAUGAUUCAAGAAGAUUACCACAGUCAAAAUCCUUACCAUAACGCAGUCCACGCUGCGGAUGUUACUCAGGCCAUGCACUGUUACUUAAAGGAACCUAAGCUUGCCAAUUCUGUAACUCCUUGGGAUAUCUUGCUGAGCUUAAUUGCAGCUGCCACUCAUGAUCUGGAUCAUCCAGGUGUUAAUCAACCUUUCCUUAUUAAAACUAACCAUUACUUGGCAACUUUAUACAAGAAUACCUCAGUACUGGAAAAUCACCACUGGAGAUCUGCAGUGGGCUUAUUGAGAGAAUCAGGCUUAUUCUCACAUCUGCCAUUAGAAAGCAGGCAACAAAUGGAGACACAGAUAGGUGCUCUGAUACUAGCCACAGACAUCAGUCGCCAGAAUGAGUAUCUGUCUUUGUUUAGGUCCCAUUUGGAUAGAGGUGAUUUAUGCCUAGAAGACACCAGACACAGACAUUUGGUUUUACAGAUGGCUUUGAAAUGUGCUGAUAUUUGUAACCCAUGUCGGACGUGGGAAUUAAGCAAGCAGUGGAGUGAAAAAGUAACGGAGGAAUUCUUCCAUCAAGGAGAUAUAGAAAAAAAAUAUCAUUUGGGUGUGAGUCCACUUUGCGAUCGUCACACUGAAUCUAUUGCCAACAUCCAGAUUGGUUUUAUGACUUACCUAGUGGAGCCUUUAUUUACAGAAUGGGCCAGGUUUUCCAAUACAAGGCUAUCCCAGACAAUGCUUGGACACGUGGGGCUGAAUAAAGCCAGCUGGAAGGGACUGCAGAGAGAACAGUCGAGCAGUGAGGACACUGAUGCUGCAUUUGAGUUGAACUCACAGUUAUUACCUCAGGAAAAUCGGUUAUCAUAACCCCCAGAACCAGUGGGACAAACUGCCUCCUGGAGGUUUUUAGAAAUGUGAAAUGGGGUCUUGAGGUGAGAGAACUUAACUCUUGACUGCCAAGGUUUCCAAGUGAGUGAUGCCAGCCAGCAUUAUUUAUUUCCAAGAUUUCCUCUGUUGGAUCAUUUGAACCCACUUGUUAAUUGCAAGACCCGAACAUACAGCAAUAUGAAUUUGGCUUUCAUGUGAAACCUUGAAUAUGCAAAGCCCAGCAGGAGAGAAUCCGAAAGGAGUAACAAAGGAAGUUUUGAUAUGUGCCACGACUUUUUCAAAGCAUCUAAUCUUCAAAACGUGAAACUUGAAUUGUUCAGCAACAAUCUCUUGGAAUUUAACCAGUCUGAUGCAACAAUGUGUAUCUUGUACCUUCCACUAAGUUCUCUCUGAGAAAAUGGAAAUGUGAAGUGCCCAGCCUCUGCUGCCUCUGGCAAGACAAUGUUUACAAAUCAACUCUGAAAAUAUUGGUUCUAAAUUGCCUUGGAGCAUGAUUGUGAAGGAACCACUCAAACAAAUUUAAAGAUCAAACUUUAGACUGCAGCUCUUUCCCCCUGGUUUGCCUUUUUCUUCUUUGGAUGCCACCAAAGCCUCCCAUUUGCUAUAGUUUUAUUUCAUGCACUGGAAACUGAGCAUUUAUCGUAGAGUACCGCCAAGCUUUCACUCCAGUGCCGUUUGGCAAUGCAAUUUUUUUUAGCAAUUAGUUUUUAAUUUGGGGUGGGAGGGGAAGAACACCAAUGUCCUAGCUGUAUUAUGAUUCUGCAGUGAAGACAUUGCAUGUUGUUUUCACUACUGUACACUUGACCUGCACAUGCGAGAAAAAGGUGGAAUGUUUAAAACACCAUAAUCAGCUCAGGGUAUUUGCCAAUCUGAAAUAAAAGUGGGAUGGGAGAGUGUGUCCUUCAGAUCAAGGGUACUAAAGUCCCUUUCGCUGCAGUGAGUGAGAGGUAUGUUGUGUGUGAAUGUACGGAUGUGUGUUUGCGUGCAUGUUUGUGCAUGUGUGACUGUGCAUGUUAUGUUUCUCCAUGUGGGCAAAGAUUUGAAAUGUAAGCUUUUAUUUAUUAUUUUAGAAUGUGACAUAAUGAGCAGCCACACUCGGGGGAGGGGAAGGUUGGUAGGUAAGCUGUAACAGAUUGCUCCAGUUGCCUUAAACUAUGCACAUAGCUAAGUGACCAAACUUCUUGUUUUGAUUUGAAAAAAGUGCAUUGUUUUCUUGUCCCUCCCUUUGAUGAAACGUUACCCUUUGACGGGCCUUUUGAUGUGAACAGAUGUUUUCUAGGACAAACUAUAAGGACUAAUUUUAAACUUCAAACAUUCCACUUUUGUAAUUUGUUUUAAAUUGUUUUAUGUAUAGUAAGCACAACUGUAAUCUAGUUUUAAGAGAAACCGGUGCUUUCUUUUAGUUCAUUUGUAUUUCCCUUGUUACUGUAAAAGACUGUUUAUUAAUUGUUUACAGUUUGUUGCAACAGCCAUUUUCUUGGGAGAAAGCUUGAGUGUAAAGCCAUUUGUAAAAGGCUUUGCCAUACUCAUUUUAAUAUGUGCCUGUUGCUGUUAACUUUUGAUGAAUAAAAACCUAUCUUUUCAUAUUUUUAUCUUUGACAUUUACCUUAUAACUCAAUCUUUUGGAAAACACAAUGCUAAAUUACAAGGAAAUCAAAGUUAGCUUCUUGGCUCUUGUAAUUCAUCCCUCAGAUGUUUACUCAGUCCGAGCUUAUCUACUAAUGACUCACCUUGCAAGUGAGUAAGCAGAAGCCCAGUUAGGGCUGUUGGAGUCCUGACUAACACAGGGGAGAGGUCAGCUUUGAGCCAGGCCUUUUGUUCCUACAGUGGUGAACUGCAUAAGACAUCAGCAAGUCUUGCAAGUACUAAAAUACUAGUUGUAUUUAUUUCUAUCAAUCAUUGGCCUUUUUAAAGUGAUAAGAAAAGGCCACUCCACUCUACUUGAUUGAUAUCAGUUGUAAACAAGGUACCACUGUGCCAUUCCCUAUAUCUUCCCAGGUCCAACUCAUUAGAAGGGAUAUGGUGCAAACUUCUAAAUCAAACACAUUAACAUAUUAUUUGUACAGAAGAGUGUUGAUGUCCAAUAGAAACAGAAUCCAAGCCACAUAAUUUUCGGUUUUCUAGUAGCCACAUUUAGAAAACAUGGAAUUAAUUUUAGUAACAUCUAUUCCAAUACGUCCAAAAUAUUGUAUCACUUUAAAAUGUCAAUAUAAAAACAAUUAGAUGUUUUUACAUUCUUUUGGGGGGUACUAAGUCUUUGAAAUCCAGUGUAUAUUGUGUACUUACAGCACAUCUCAAUUUGGACUAGUCAUAUCUCAGGCACCCAAUAUCCACAUGUGGCUAGUGGCUACCAUAUUGGACAGUGUGGGUAUAGAGGUCUGAGGGUAGUAGAGGAAUAUGGUCAGCUGGUCACUCUCGUGAGAUGGCCAUACCUUGGCCUAUAUUUAAUGUGUACAGAAAGUCUGAUAACUCAGAUCCUUAAAAAUUCAGGCCCACUGUUUCAGUACAUAGAGAGUGGAACUAUCAUGGCAAACCCACAUUAACCAAGCUCACAGUAACUAUUUUUUUAAAACACUAUCAAUAUUUUAAUUUACAGUGAGAAAUGUAACUAUCAAUUAUUCUCUCCCUUUAGGCAAAUCUUCCUGGGAAGCCAAAUUAUGAGCAGCUGGUGAGCAUGGAUUCUGAGCAAGGGAAGCAAGUUGCCUCGUGCACCCAUGUCCCUUUGGGUGCACAGAAGACCCAUGUCUUCUGUGAUAUUCAUGUUUGUGGACCAGGGUACCCUCUUCCCCUGGAAGGUGCUAGAGAUUCUCUGCCAGUAGUUGCUUCUCUACAUCAGCUUCUGAUUGGCACAUGCAUUAAAUAACGUCAUUACCUCAAGCCUUGUUUCAGUUGAGCUUACCUGGGCUCCAUUCUGCCUGUAUACAUGAUUGCUUCUGCUCUGAUCCAUUGUUUCUCUUAUAGUUUGAAACUGAAAAGAUCAUCCUAUUUCCACAUUCUCAGGGGAACUGUGGGUGUGGCUCCCAUUUCCUGCCUACACAUAUAAUAAACCCAUUGAAAAGUUGUUUUAUUAUGUAUAUGUGGGAAUCACCUUCUAUAGCCCUUUUGUUUUUUUUUUUUUUUGAGACAGGGUCUCGCUGCUAACUAGGCUGGAGUGCAGUGGCAUGAUCACUGCAGCCUCCACCUCCUAGGCUCAAGCAAUCCUCCCACCUCAGCCUCCUGAGUGCCACCACACCACCCAGCUAAUUUUUUUUUUUUUUUUUUUUUUUUUUUUUGAGACAGAGCCUUGCUCUGUCGCCCAGGCUGGAGUGCAGUGCCGCGAUAUUGGCUCACUGCAAGUUCCGCCUCCCGGGUUCACGCCAUUCUCCUCAUUCUCCUGCCUCAGUCUCCCAGGUCGCUGGGACUACAGGCGCCCGCCACCAGGCCCUGCUAAUUUUUUUGUACUUUAUUAGUAGAGUUAGGGUUUCACCAUGUUAGCCAGGAUGGUCUCAAUCUCCUGACCUCGUGAUCCGCCCGCCUCGGCCUCCCAUAGUGCUGGGAUUACAGGCGUGAGCCACCGUGCCCGGCCAGCUAAUUUUUUAAGAACAUUUUUGUGGCCGGGCAUGGUGGCUCACACCUGUAAUCCCAGCACUUUGGGAGGCUGAGGUGGGUGGAUCACCUGAGGUCGGGAGUUCGAGACCAGUCUGGCCAACAUGGUGAAACCCCAUCUCUACUAAAAAUGCAAAAAUUAGCUGGGCGUGGUGGCGCAUUCCUGUAAUCCCAGCUACUCGGGAGGCUGAGGCGGAAGAAUUGCUUGAACCCAGGUGGCGGAGGUUGCAAGGAGCAGAGAUUGUGCUACUGCACUCCAGCCUAGGUGACAGAGCAAGACUCUGUCUCAAAAAAAAAAAAAAAACUUUUUUAUAGAGACAGGGUCUCUCUUUGUUGGCUUGGCUGGUCUUGAACUCUUGGGCUCAAGCAGUCCUGCCACCGUGGCCUCUCAAAGUGCUGGGAUUACAGGUGUGAGACACUGCAUCAGGCCUAUAGCUCCACUUAAAUACGACCUAUAUUACUGGAAUAUUUUUUUCUAAAAAAUUUUAGGAAACAGUUAAAUAUUUAAAAGAUUACUUUUUUAAAAAGCAAGUAAAUAUUACAGAACAGAAUGCAAAAUUUAUUUUACAUGGGAGACUAAAAAUUUUCACACACAUGGCCACCCUUUGGGCCUCUUGGCUCAACAUUUCAGGGGCUGAGGGAGUCUCUGCUCUAGGAGUAAAAGGUCCUUGGAGAGAAAAUUUUGACAAGUCCUAACUUUAAAAAAGAAAAAUUGGUUCCUGGUCAAUAUUUGUACUCACUGUAAAUGUGAUGGUUGGUAAUGAUACUCUGUAUAAAAGUAAAAAUCAUAUUUUAUGUCCUUUGCAAACAAAUAUAUUUGUACCUGAGGUACAGAUUAGAGGUGCUAGUAAUUCCUUGAAGAUUCUGAAAAUGAUCUUUUUUUCCAAAAUGCUUUCUUGGUUUUUAUUAAACUUUCUAUUUUCUUAAAACUCUCACAUCAGGUAUUUCCAGUGUUUUCAAGCAUGUAUAAAUAUUUUAAUGUAUAAAUGUUGUUUAAAAUCCCCUCAAUCGGUAUCUCCUGAUUGAGAAAAUACACAGUGACCAAUAGCUAAUAGGAAUUCAGUAUUGCUUUCAAAGAAAUGUGCAUAUUAAUCACUGUAGCAUCUGCAUACAUUUGAAACACGGAGUAAUACAGGUCUGUGCAAGAAUUAGCAGCUUGUUCCUUGCUAAUAAUGACUUGUGUCAUCUGGAAGGCCCCCAAGAGCCCAUGGUCUACAGGUGGAAUGACCACCACUUGGGAGUGAGCUGAUGGAGAGCACCCAGCAGGUCUCCUCCAUCUUCCUGGUUCCUGUGCUCACCAUAGGGCUGGUGUACAUUGGGCCAUUAAUAAACGUUUGUUGAACAAAUUAA